AGUCUCUGGUGGCUAGCCUGUCCUGACAGGGGAGAGUUAAGCUCCCGUUCUCCACCGUGCCGGCUGGCCAGGUGGGCUGAGGGUGACCGAGAGACCAGAACCUGCUUGCUGGAGCUUAGUGCUCAGAGCUGGGGAGGGAGGUUCCGCCGCUCCUCUGCUGUCAGCGCCGGCAGCCCCUCCCGGCUUCACUUCCUCCCGCAGCCCCUGCUACUGAGAAGCUCCGGGAUCCCAGCAGCCGCCACGCCCUGGCCUCAGCCUGCGGGGCUCCAGUCAGGCCAACACCGACGCGCAGCUGGGAGGAAGACAGGACCCUUGACAUCUCCAUCUGCACAGAGGUCCUGGCUGGACCGAGCAGCCUCCUCCUCCUAGGAUGACCUCACCCUCCAGCUCUCCAGUUUUCAGGUUGGAGACAUUAGAUGGAGGCCAAGAAGAUGGCUCUGAGGCGGACAGAGGAAAGCUGGAUUUUGGGAGCGGGCUGCCUCCCAUGGAGUCACAGUUCCAGGGCGAGGACCGGAAAUUCGCCCCUCAGAUAAGAGUCAACCUCAACUACCGAAAGGGAACAGGUGCCAGUCAGCCGGAUCCAAACCGAUUUGACCGAGAUCGGCUCUUCAAUGCGGUCUCCCGGGGUGUCCCCGAGGAUCUGGCUGGACUUCCAGAGUACCUGAGCAAGACCAGCAAGUACCUCACCGACUCGGAAUACACAGAGGGCUCCACAGGUAAGACGUGCCUGAUGAAGGCUGUGCUGAACCUUAAGGACGGAGUCAAUGCCUGCAUUCUGCCACUGCUGCAGAUCGACAGGGACUCUGGCAAUCCUCAGCCCCUGGUAAAUGCCCAGUGCACAGAUGACUAUUACCGAGGCCACAGCGCUCUGCACAUCGCCAUUGAGAAGAGGAGUCUGCAGUGUGUGAAGCUCCUGGUGGAGAAUGGGGCCAAUGUGCAUGCCCGGGCCUGCGGCCGCUUCUUCCAGAAGGGCCAAGGGACUUGCUUUUAUUUCGGUGAGCUACCCCUCUCUUUGGCCGCUUGCACCAAGCAGUGGGAUGUGGUAAGCUACCUCCUGGAGAACCCACACCAGCCCGCCAGCCUGCAGGCCACUGACUCCCAGGGCAACACAGUCCUGCAUGCCCUAGUGAUGAUCUCGGACAACUCAGCUGAGAACAUUGCACUGGUGACCAGCAUGUAUGAUGGGCUCCUCCAAGCUGGGGCCCGCCUCUGCCCUACCGUGCAGCUUGAGGACAUCCGCAACCUGCAGGAUCUCACGCCUCUGAAGCUGGCCGCCAAGGAGGGCAAGAUCGAGAUUUUCAGGCACAUCCUGCAGCGGGAGUUUUCAGGACUGAGCCACCUUUCCCGAAAGUUCACCGAGUGGUGCUAUGGGCCUGUCCGGGUGUCGCUGUAUGACCUGGCUUCUGUGGACAGCUGUGAGGAGAACUCAGUGCUGGAGAUCAUUGCCUUUCAUUGCAAGAGCCCGCACCGACACCGAAUGGUCGUUUUGGAGCCCCUGAACAAACUGCUGCAGGCGAAAUGGGAUCUGCUCAUCCCCAAGUUCUUCUUAAACUUCCUGUGUAAUCUGAUCUACAUGUUCAUCUUCACCGCUGUUGCCUACCAUCAGCCUACCCUGAAGAAGGCCGCCCCUCACCUGAAAGCGGAGGUUGGAAACUCCAUGCUGCUGACGGGCCACAUCCUUAUCCUGCUAGGGGGGAUCUACCUCCUCGUGGGCCAGCUGUGGUACUUCUGGCGGCGCCACGUGUUCAUCUGGAUCUCGUUCAUAGACAGCUACUUUGAAAUCCUCUUCCUGUUCCAGGCCCUGCUCACAGUGGUGUCCCAGGUGCUGUGUUUCCUGGCCAUCGAGUGGUACCUGCCCCUGCUUGUGUCUGCGCUGGUGCUGGGCUGGCUGAACCUGCUUUACUAUACACGUGGCUUCCAGCACACAGGCAUCUACAGUGUCAUGAUCCAGAAGGUGUCCACACGGGAGCAUGUGCAUCCUUCCACAAGCAAGGAGCAAAGAAUAUGUGCAUAAGCUCAUCUGCAUGUCUGUGUCCUGCGAUGUGUGGGCGCGGGCAUGUAACUGCAUUCAUUUAUGUAUUCAGCGCAUGUUUAGGGAGUGCCUACUGUGGGCCGGGCCCUGUUCUAGGUGUUGGGAAUAUAGCAGAGAACAGAACAAGUCCUUGCUCCCCUGAAGCUGAUGUUCUGGUGGGAGGAAAUGAAAACCUUAAGAAAACAACUGAGAACAUUCCACACUGCUAAAUUCUAUGAAGGAAAAAAAAGCACAGGACAAUGUGAUGCAGAAUGGCUGGGACCAAGUACCCUUUAGAUGGGAUGGUCUGGGAAGCCUCUCUAAAGAGGGGAUGUUUAAGUUGAGACCUGAAAGAAUGAUUCAGCCACAGCAGGGUGAAGAGGAGAUAUUCUCAGCAGAGGGCACAGCAGUGGCUGCCACGAGCCAGAAGGAGCUUGGGGUGCUUGGGACAGGGUGAGGAGGCUAGGUGGCUGGGGAGAUGGCAGGAGGGUGGAGGUGAGGAGGUUGGGAGGAAGGGAAGGGCCAGGGGCCCCUUCCACGGGGAGGGAUUUGGAGGUCCCCAGAGGCUUUUUUUUUUUUAAUUGUAGUAAAAUACACCUAACAUGGAACUUUUUUUUUUUUCUUUGAGAUGGAGUCUCACUCUUGUUACCUAGGCUAGAGUGCAAUGGCACCAUCUCAGCUCACUGCAAACCCCUACUCCUGGGUUCAAGCGAUUCUCCUGCCUCAGCCUCCCGUAUGGCUGGGGUUGCAGGCACCCACCACCAUGCCCGGCUAAUUUUUGUAUUUUUAGUAGAGACAGGUUUUCACCACGUUGGCCAGGCUGGUCUCAAACUCCUGACCUCAGGUGAUCCGCCUGCCUUGGCCUCCCAAAGUGCUGGGAUUACAGGCAUGAGCUACUGCGCCUGGCCCAUUUUAACCUUUUUUUUUUAAAGUAUACAGCUAAGUGUCAUUAAGUACAUUCACACUGUUGUAUAACCAUCACCACCAUCCAACUCCAGAACUUUCUUGUCAUCCCAAACUGAAACUCAACACCCAUUAAACAACUCCCCAUUCCCUUCCCCCA